CGCGCCACUGCACUCCAGCCUGGGCGACAAAGUGAGACUCCAGUCUCAAAAAACAAAACAAAACAAAAAACAACAGUUAAGAGAGUUCUUUCUGGCCCAUUUAGAUCUGCUAGCCCUACUUUUGAAGAGGAAACUUUUGAAGGAAUGAACAAAAGAGUAUUCACCACAUGGAGUGCAGUGAGGCAGUUCCAGAACUCAAGGUAAUAAUGUAAGCAUAUUAAUAAUAUUUAAUUAUUAACAAUUAAUAAUUAAUCAAUUAAUAACAUAUGCAUAUGAGAUCAGCAGGAGUCACACUAAAAGCCAAAAAGCAUUUCAGGUGAAAAACAGCAAGGGUAGGCCAGAAAACACAAAGAAAUCUUGACUGAAAAGUCAGCAAUAAAAAACACUAUUGAAUAAAAAGGAAGGCUCGAUAUACUAGGGCUGGCAGGGGAGCCAAGCAAGUAGAUCCAGAGCCAGAAUGACAGCAGGGACCUGGUAGGCCUUGCUUGUUAUCUCCAGCAACCAGCCCCACGCUUAGCAAACAGUAUUCUGCAUCCUGUAUGAUUGCAGGUAUAUUCCAAAUGUGGGGAUGAAGGCAACUAGUAUUUACAGUCCAAUGCCACCAGCCAUGAGGAUGACCCAUCUUGGCUGAAAAAUAAAGACCUUAAAUCUAGGAAGCGGAAGAUACAACCCAGGACAGCAGGAAGGGGAGACCCGGUAUGAGAAGAACUGAGGCCCAACCCAGUUUAGAGAGGAGACUGAAGGCUAAAGGAGGAAGGUUUCCCAGGAAAAAAAAAAUUAGGAUUUGAAAGUUGAUGCUAUCUUUGAUAAUUUGGAACAACGUAAAUAAGUAGAAAUGGCAGGGCCGGGCGCCGUGGCUCACGCCUGUAAUCCCAGCACUUUGGGAGGCUGAGGCGGGAGGAUCACCUGAGGUCGGGAGUUCGAGACCAGCCUGACUUAAUAUGGAGAAACCCCGUCUCUACUAAAAAUACAAAAUUAGACGGGCAUGGUGGCUCAUGCCUGUAAUCCCAGCUACUUGGGAGGCUGAGGCAGGAGAAUCGCUUGAACCUGGGAGGCGAAGGUUGCGGUGAGCCUAGAUAGCGCCAUUGCACUCCAGCCUGGGCAAGCCGAGAUAGCGCCAUUGCACUCCAGCCUGGGCAACAAGAGUAAAACUCCUUCUCAAAGAAAAAGUAGAAAUGGCUGGGAACCGUGGCGCAUGCCUGUAAUCACAGCACUUUGGGAGGCCGAGGCAGGAGAAUUGCUUGAGGCCAGGAGUUCCAGACCAGCCUGGGCAACAUAGCAAGACCCUGUCUCUGUUUUAAAAUUUAAAAAUUAGCCAAGCAUUGGGUGUGCGCCUGUGGUCCCAGCUACUCGGGAGGCUGAGGUGAGAAGAUCGCUUCAGCCCGGGAGGUCGAGUCUGCAGUGAGCUAGGAUCGCACUGCUGGGCCACAGAGCAAGACCCUGUCUCAAAACAAACAAAAAAUAAAUUCAUGUAUGUUAGCAACAAUUACUAUUUAAUUUAAAACUUCCCCAUUCCGAUUCCAUCCUCACCAAGCACGUUCCUUCGCCUGCAGCUUCGGUCUAGAGCCUGAGCGAGCCGAGCUGCGGAUGCCAGGGGCUGGGUGGACUCCGCAGCUAAGCUACUGUAAAACACGCACCUGCUUCUACCGCGGGUGUACACAUGGUUUGCCAGGGUGUGCGCGUCUUCCCAAGGGGUCUGGGGACCAAAUUCCAGCUCCCGCCAUCGGGAGGCACGGUAAGAGACCGUAGGGGACACAAUCCCGAGCACCGCAGAUGCCGAGGUCUCCGCUGCGCUCCAGUCUGUCAACAGAGGCUUCAGGACCGCGGGGUCCCUUCAAAUGCCCCGCCAGUCCCAGGCCAAUCACCGCGCAGCUUCUUCCGGGAUCGUCGCCAAUCAUCGGCCGUUGCGUAUUGCGGGUACAGAGGGGAUUCCCAGGCCCCAAACCAGCCCUCAUCUCUUGGAUGGAACAGGAGAGUGAGGCUUGGAGCCCCGCCGCCCAGGAUCCUGAGAAGGGGGAAAGACUGGGAGGAGCUCGGAGAGGAGAUGUCCCAAACAGGAAGGAAGAGGAACCGGAGGAAGUCCCAAGAGCCAAAGGGCCUAGAAAGGCUCCUGUGAAGGAGAGUCCUGAAGUGCUGGUGGAACGCAACCCUGACCCAGCUAUUAGCGUGGCCCCGGCACGGGCACAGCCACCCAAAAAUGCUGCCUGGGACCCGACCACAGGAGCACAGCCCCCGGCACCCAUACCCAGCAUGGAUGCUCAGGCCGGCCAGCGGCGCCACGUGUGCACGGACUGCGGCCGCCGCUUCACCUACCCCUCACUGCUGGUCAGCCACAGGCGCAUGCACUCGGGGGAGCGGCCUUUCCCCUGCCCCGAGUGUGGCAUGCGCUUCAAGAGGAAGUUCGCAGUGGAAGCGCACCAGUGGAUCCACCGCUCCUGCUCCGGGGGGCGGCGGGGCCGGAGGCCUGGGAUCCGGGCUGUGCCUCGGGCCCCCGUCCGAGGUGACCGGGACCCGCCUGUGCUCUUCCGGCACUACCCAGACAUCUUCGAGGAGUGCGGCUGAGCGGCACCGCAGGCUGGAGUUGAGCCUGACCUUGGCACGAAGGACUGACGGAUCCCUGAGGUGGGCCACUGAGUCGGGGACUCCGGAACUGAAAUUCAUGCCCUGGGCUUUCCUCAAGGAUCCCUCAAGUUUCCAACUUGUAAAAAGAAAAGUGCCUGUAAAGAUUCGAAUAGAUUAGACUUGCCACCCA